AUGGGGCUCAUUCCUCACAACGGCCUUUCCCGGCCCAGUUUUUCCCUUCCGGCGGCCUCUCCGGGCCCAGAAGCUCCUCAAGUCGGCCUCUCCAGACCCACUUGCAGCCUCCCGGCGUCCUCUCCGGGCCCAGCUCUUCCUCCCGGCUGCGUCUGCAGGCCCGACUCCUGCCUCCCAACAACGUCUUUGGACUCAGUGCCUGCCCAGCUCGUGGUGGCCUUGGUCGGCCCACAGCUUCCUCAAGCCAAGCUCCCCAGGCCCAGCUCAGGCCUCACGGUGGCCUCUCCAGGCUCAGCUCCUGCCCUCCGACGGCGUCUCCAGGCCCCAAACGGCCUCCGGUCGGUGGGCUUCUCCAGGCCCAGCUUGGGCCUCCCGGCGGCCUCUGCAGGCCCAAGUGGUCCUGAAGGCAGCCUCUCCAGGCCCAGCUCCGGCCUCCCAGCAAGCAAGCUCUUUUGGCUCAGCUCCUGCCCAGCUCCCGCCGGCUUUUGUAGACCCUGAACUUUCUCCAG